AGAAGAAGAGGAAGUGAAGGCUACAGGGUAUCCACGUGGGUUCUGAGCGUGUUUCUACGUCCCUGGAAGCCGGUCAUUUAAGCUCAUUCCUCGCCACGGCUUAGUCAACAUGGGUCGCUCGGGAAAGUUGCCUUCUGGUGUCUCAGCUAAGUUGAAGCGCUGGAAGAAAGGCCACAGCAGCGACAGCAACCCCGCCAUCUGCCGCCACCGUCAGGCCGCCCGCAGCCGCUUCUUCAGCCGGCCGUCAGGAAGGAGUGACCUGACAGUCGAUGCUGUGAAGUUACAUAAUGAGCUGCAGUCAGGGUCCUUGCGCUUGGGCAAAAGCGAAGCCCCGGAGACGCCCAUGGAAGAAGAGGCGGAGCUGGUUCUCACCGAGAAGUCCUCGGGUACCUUCCUGAGUGGCCUUUCCGACUGCACAAACGUCACCUUCAGCAAAGUACAGCGCUUCUGGGAGUCCAACUCGGCUGCCCACAAGGAGAUCUGUGCUGUUCUGGCUGCUGUCACUGAGGUGAUUCGCUCCCAGGGAGGGAAGGAGACGGAGACUGAGUACUUCGCUGCUCUGAUCCGGAAGGCUGCCCAGCAUGGAGUAUGCUCAGUCCUCAAGGGCAGUGAAUUCAUGUUUGAAAAGGCCCCUGCCCAUCAUCCUGCUGCCAUUUCCACUGCCAAGUUCUGCAUCCAGGAGAUUGAGAAGUCUGGAGGCUCCAAGGAGGCCACCACCACGCUGCACAUGCUGACGCUGCUGAAGGACCUGCUGCCCUGCUUCCCGGAAGGCCUGGUGAAGAGCUGCAGUGAGACUCUCCUCAGGGUCAUGACCUUGAGCCAUGUGCUGGUGACAGCCUGUGCCAUGCAGGCCUUUCACAGCCUCUUCCACGCCAGGCCUGGCCUGAGCACCCUGUCAGCAGAGCUCAACGCCCAGAUCAUCACGGCCCUGUACGACUAUGUUCCCAGUGAGAAUGAUUUACAACCCCUGCUAGCCUGGCUUAAGGUCAUGGAGAAAGCCCACAUCAACCUGGUGAGGUUGCAGUGGGACCUGGGGCUAGGCCACCUCCCUCGCUUUUUUGGAACUGCGGUGACCUGCCUCCUUUCCCCACACUCGCAAGUGCUGACUGCUGCUACGCAGAGCCUCAAGGAGAUCCUGAAGGAAUGCGUGGCUCCCCACAUGGCUGACAUUGGCUCCGUGACCUCCUCGGCCUCAGGCCCUGCCCAAUCUGUUGCCAAGAUGUUCAGGGCAGUGGAGGAGGGCCUGACGUACAAAUUCCAUGCGGCCUGGAGCUCCGUGUUGCAGCUGCUGUGUGUCUUCUUCGAGGCGUGUGGGAGACAGGCCCACCCUGUGAUGAGGAAGUGCCUCCAGUCCCUGUGUGACCUGCGCCUCUCCCCUCAUUUCCCCCACACGGCGGCUCUUGACCAGGCAGUGGGGGCUGCGGUGACCAGUAUGGGACCUGAGGUGGUGCUGCAGGCUGUGCCUUUGGAAAUUGAUGGCUCUGAGGAGACUCUGGAUUUCCCACGGAGCUGGCUGCUGCCUGUCAUCCGAGACCAUGUUCAGGAAACGCGACUUGGUUUUUUCACCACCUACUUCUUGCCCCUGGCUAACACCCUGAAGAGCAAAGCCAUGGACCUGGCUCAGGCAGGCAGCACAGUGGAAUCUAAGAUCUACGACACACUCCAGUGGCAGAUGUGGACACUCCUGCCUGGGUUCUGCACAAGGCCUACAGAUGUGGCCAUCUCCUUCAAAGGGCUGGCACGGACGCUGGGCAUGGCCAUCAGCGAGCGUCCAGACCUGAGGGUCACCGUGUGCCAGGCCCUGCGCACCCUCAUCACCAAGGGCUGCCAGGCAGAGGCUGACCGUGCUGAAGUGAGUCGCUUUGCCAAGAACUUUCUGCCGAUCCUCUUCAACCUGUAUGGGCAGCCCGUGGCAGCCGGGGACACUCCAGCCCCUCGCCGGGCUGUGCUGGAAACCAUCAGAACUUACCUCACCAUCACUGACACUCAGUUGGUGAACAGUCUCCUGGAAAAAGCCAGUGAGAAGGUGCUCGACCCUGCCAGCUCUGACUUUACCAGAUUGUCUGUCCUGGACCUGGUCGUGGCCUUGGCUCCGUGUGCUGACGAAGCUGCCAUCAGUAAGCUAUACUCCACCAUCCGGCCCUACCUAGAGAGCAAGGCCCACGGGGUGCAGAAGAAGGCCUACCGAGUGCUGGAGGAGGUGUGUGCCAGUCCUCAGGGCCCCGGGGCCCUCUUCGUGCAGAGCCACCUGGAGGACCUGAAGAAGACACUGCUGGACUCGCUGCGGAGCACCUCCUCACCCGCCAAGAGGCCCCGUUUGAAGUGCCUCCUACACAUCGUGAGGAAGCUCUCAGCUGAACACAAGGAGUUCAUCACUGCCCUCAUCCCAGAGGUGAUCCUGUGCACCAAGGAGGUGUCGGUGGGCGCACGGAAGAACGCUUUUGCACUGCUCGUGGAGAUGGGCCAUGCUUUCCUAAGGUUUGGCUCGAACCAGGAAGAGGCCCUGCAGUGCUACCUCGUCCUGAUCUACCCUGGCCUGGUGGGCGCGGUGACCAUGGUCAGCUGCAGCAUCCUGGCCCUGACCCACCUCCUUUUCGAGUUUAAAGGUCUGAUGGGGACCAGUACAGUGGAGCAGCUGCUGGAGAAUGUGUGCCUGCUUCUGGCCUCCCGCACCCGUGACGUGGUCAAGUCUGCACUGGGCUUCAUCAAGGUGGCAGUGACUGUCAUGGACGUGGCGCACCUGGCCAAACAUGUGCAGCUGGUGAUGGAAGCCAUUGGGAAGCUUUCAGAUGACAUGCGGCGGCACUUCCGCAUGAAGCUUCGGAACCUGUUCACCAAGUUCAUCCGCAAGUUUGGAUUUGAGCUGGUGAAAAGGCUGUUGCCCGAGGAGUACCACAGAGUCCUGGUCAACAUCCGGAAAGCUGAGGCCCGGGCCAAGAGGCACCGAGCCCUGAGCCAGGCUGCCGUGGAGGAGGAAGAAGAGGAGGAGGAGGAGGAGGAGCCCGCCCAGGGCAAAGGUGACAGCAUUGAGGAGAUUUUAGCUGACUCAGAGGACGAGGAGGACAAUGAGGAGGAGGAAAGAAGCCGAGGCAAGGAGCAGCGGAAGCUGGCACGACAGAGGAGCCGGGCAUGGCUGAAAGAGGGCGGUGGGGACGAGCCCCUCAACUUCCUGGAUCCCAAGGUGGCCCAACGAGUCCUGGCCACGCAGCCAGGGCCAGGCCGGGGCAGGAAGAAGGACCACGGCUUCAAGGUGAGCGCCGAUGGCCGGCUGAUCAUAAGGGAGGAGGCAGACGGCAACAAGAUGGAGGAAGAGGAAGGUGCCAAAGGCGAAGAUGAAGAGAUGGCUGACCCAAUGGAAGAUGUGAUCAUCAGGAAUAAAAAGCACCAGAAGCUCAAGCACCAGAAAGAGGCUGAGGAGGAGGAGCUGGAGAUACCCCCUCAGUACCAAGCUGGAGGCUCUGGCAUUCAUCGCCCUGUGGCCAAGAAGGCUAUGCCUGGGGCUGAAUACAAGGCCAAGAAAGCAAAAGGUGAUGUGAAGAAGAAAGGCCGGCCGGAUCCCUAUGCCUACAUCCCCCUCAACAGAAGCAAGCUCAACCGCAGGAAGAAGAUGAAGCUGCAGGGACAGUUCAAAGGCCUGGUGAAGGCUGCCCGGCGAGGUUCCCAGGUGGGACACAAAAACCGCAGAAAGGAUCGUCGACCCUGAGGCCCAGGGCCCCUGGGCUGCCCUGUGGUCCAGUCUGAGGCCCUUUCAGCCCCCAGGCUGCCUUGCCACCAGCUCCAGGUGCUCAAGAUUCUGGCAGAGCCUGGACUCAGGAUGACUUGGAACUAGGGCUUGGCUCUCAGAAGUCCUGGAUUUUGGAAACUCCAAAUGGAAUCACCCUUCAGAGACAUCCCUGGUGCCUGGAGAUGGGAAUGUGGCCUCAGUGCCUCUGAGUAGGUGCCAUGAGGCACCUUUGCUUUCUGCCCAGAGUGGCCAUGAGCACCAGAACAGAUGAUCUCCAUUUCCGCCAGCUGCCUGUAGCCACGUGGCAUCCUGCCUGUGGUCUGGGUGAGAUUUACUGUGACCAGAUGUAGAAUAAAUGUGUCUCAUCCUGCAUUUUUUUUCUAGAAACUGUUUCAUAGUCUGCCCCCUCCAGGGGUAAGAACAGUGUGCAGUUGUUGGCAGCAGUGGCCUGACCUCUUCCUGUCUAACUCCUUACAUCCAGUCCAGGGCAUAUCAUAAGGCUUUGCCCAUAGGACAGGCUUUGGAACUUGCCCGGGAGCACCCACCUGUGUCAGGAGGGGCAGCGAAUGCCCCAGGGCUGGUGUCGGGAGCUGCAGUUCAGCACCAGGGACUGCCCCAGCUGUCCUGGGCACAAGUCUCUCCAGCAUCUUUGUUCAUUGAUUCAACAAAGUAUUUGCUGAGCCCCUCUAAGUGCCCAGCAUAGCCUUGUUCAUUCA